AUGAGGAGCCAUCUCACUAUUGACCGGCUAGUGCCGGCUCCCUAUGAGGACACUGUACACGACAUCGCUAAUGAGGACGCUGUAUAUGACAUUGCUACUGAGGACGCCAUAUAUGACAUCGCUAACGAGGACGCCGUCCAGGGCAUCGCAAAGGAGGACGCCGCCCAGGGCAUCGCUAACGAGGAAGCCGUCCACGACAUCGCUAACGAGGAUGCCGCCCACGUAAUCGCUAACGAGGACGCCGCCCAGAGCAUCGCUAACGAGGACGCGGUCCACGACAUCGCUAACGAGGAUGCCACCCAGGGCAUCGUUAAUGAGGACGCCGCCCACAAUAUCGCUAAUGAGGACGCCGCCCACGGCGUCGCUAACGAGGUCGCCGCCCAGGGCGUCGCUAACGAGGACGCCGUCCACUGCAUCGCUAACGAGGUCGCCGCCCAGGGCGUCCUUAAAGAGGACGCCGCCCAGGACAUCGCAAACGAGGACGCCGCCCAGGGCAUCGCUAACGAGGACGCCGCCCACGGCAUCGCAAACGAGGACGCAGCCCAGGACAUCGCAAACGAGGACGCCGCCCAGGACAUCGCAAACGAGGACGCCGCCCAGGGCAUCUCUAAGGAGGACGCCGUCCAGGGCAUCGCGAACGAGGAUGCCGCCCAGGGCAUCGCUAAGGAGGACCCCGUCCAGGGCGUCGCUAACGAGGACCCCGUCCAGGGCGUCAAUAACGAGGACGCCGUCCAGGGCAUCGCUAAGGAGGACCCCGUCCAGGGCGUCGCUAACGAGGACCCCGUCCAGGGCGUCGCUAACGAGGACGCCGUCCAGGGCAUCGCUAACGAGGACGCCGUCCACGGCGUCGCUAAAGAGGUCGCCGCCCACGGCGUCGCUAACGAGGAUGCCGCCCACGCGAUCGCUAAGCCGGACGCCGCCCGCGGCAUCGCUAACGAGGUUGCCGCCCAGGGCAUCGCUACCGAGGACGUCGCCGACGGCAUCGCUAACGAGGACGCCGCCCACGGCGUCGCUAACGAGGUCGCCGCCCAGGGCGUCGCUAACGAGGACGCCGUCGAGGGCGUCGCUAACGAGGACGCCGCCCAGGGCGUCGCUAAAGAGGUCACCGCCCACGGCGUCGCUAACGAGGACGCCGUCCAGGGUCGCCAUCCACAGCAUCGCUAUCGAGGACACCACACCGUCCAGGGCGUGGCUAACGAGGUCGCUGCCCAGGGCAUCGCUACCGAGGAUGUCGCCGACGGCAUCGCUGAGGACGCCGCCCAUGGCAUCACUAACAAGGAGGCCGCCCAGGCCAUCGCUAAGCAGGAUGCCGCCCACGGCAUCACUAACGAGGACGCCGUCCAGGGCGUCGCUAACGAGGUCGCCGCCCAGGGCGUCGCUAACGAGGACGCCGCCCACGGCGUCGCUAACGAGGUCGCCGCCCACGGCGUCGCUAACGAGGACGCCGCCCAGGGCGUCGCUAACGAGGUCGCCGCCCAGGGCGUCGCUAACGAGGACGCCGCCCAGGGCGUCGCUAACGAGGACGCCGUCCAGGGCGUCGCUAACGAGGUCGAAGUCCAGGGCAUCGCACACAAGGACGCCAUCCAGGGCAUCGCUAACGAGGAUGCCGCCCACGGCAUCGCUAACGAGGUCGCCGCCCACGGCAUCGCAAACGAGGACGCUGCCCAGGGCAUCGCGAACGAGGACGCCGCCCAGGGCAUCGCUAACGAGGUCGCCGCCCACGGCAUCUCUAAGGAGGACACCGUCCAGGGCAUCGCGAACGAGGACGCCGCCCAGGGCAUCGCUAAAGAGAACCCCGUCCAGGGCGUCGCUAACGAGGACCCUGUCCAGGGCGUCGCUAACGAGGUUGAAGUCCAGGGCGUCGCACACGAGGACGCCGUCCAGGGCAUCGCUAACGAGGACGCCGCCCACGGCAUCGCGAACGAGGUCGCUGCCCAGGGCAUCGCGAACGAGGACGCCGCCCAGGACAUCGCAAAGGAGGAUGCCGCCCAGGACAUCGCAAACGAGGACGCCGCCCAGGGCAUCUCUAAGGAGGACGCCGUCCAGGGCAUCGCGAACGAGGACGCCGCCCAGGGCAUCGCUAAGGAGGACCCCGUCCAGGGCGUCGCUAACGAGGACGCCGUCCAGGGCGUCGCUAACGAGGUUGAAGUCCAGGGCGUCGCACACGAGGACGCCGUCCAGGGCAUCGCUAACGAGGACGCCGCCCACGGCAUCACUAACGAGGUCGCCGCCCACGGCAUCGCGAACGAGGACGCCGCCCAGGGCAUAGCACAUGAGGAUGCCGUCCAGGGCAUCGCUAACGAGGACGCCGUCCACGGCGUCGCUAAAGAGGUCGCCGCCCACGGCGUCGCUAACGAGGAUGCCGCCCACGCGAUCGCUAAGCCGGAUGCCGCCCACGGCAUCGCUAACGAGGUCGCCACCCAGGGCAUCGCUACCGAGGAUGUCGCCGACGGCAUCGCUAAUGAGGACGCCGCCCACGGCGUCGCUAAAGAGGUCACCGCCCACGGCGUCGCUAACGAGGACGCCGUCCAGGGCGUCGUUAACGAGGACGCCCUCCACGGCGUCGUCGCUAACGAGGAUGCCGCCCAAGCGAUCGCUAAGCCGGACGCCGCCCAUGGCAUCGCUAACGAGGUCGCCGCCCACGGCAUCGCGAACGAGGACGCCGCCCAGGGCAUCGCUAACGAGGUCGCCGCCCACGGCAUCUCUAAGGAGGACGCUGUCCAGGGCAUCGCGAACGAGGACGCCGCCCAGGGCAUCGCGAACGAGGACGCCGCCCAGGGCAUCGCACACGAGGACGCCGUCCAGGGCAUCGCUAACGAGGACGCCGUCCACGGCGUCGCUAAAGAGGUCGCCGCCCACGGCGUCGCUAACAAGGAUGCCGCCCACGCGAUCGCUAAGCCGGACGCCGCCCGCGGCAUCGCUAACGAGGUUGCCGCCCAGGGCAUCGCUACCGAGGAUGUCGCCGACGGCAUCGCUAACAAGGACGCCGUCCACGGCGUCGCUAACGAGGUCGCCGCCCACGGCGUCGCUAACGAGGAUGCCGCCCACGCGAUCGCUAAGCCGGAUGCCGCCCACGGCAUCGCUAACGAGGUCGCCACCCAGGGCAUCGCUACCGAGGAUGUCGCCGACGGCAUCGCUAACGAGGACGCCGCCCACGGCGUCGCUAACGAGGUCGCCGCCCACGGCGUCGCUAUCGAGGACGCCGUCCAGGGCGUCGCUAACGAGGACGCCGUCCACGGCGUCGCUAACGAGGACGCCGCCCAGGGCGUCGCUAAAGAGGUCACCGCCCACGGCGUCGCUAACGAGGACGCCGUCCAGGGCGUCGUUAAUGAGGACGCCCUCCACAGCGUCUUCGCUAACGAGGAUGCCGCCCAAGCGAUCGCUAAGCCGGACGCCGCCCAUGGCAUCGCUAACGAGGUCGCCGCCCACGGCAUCGGGAACGAGGACGCUGCCCAGGGCAUCGCGAACGAGGACGCCGCCCAGGGCAUCGCUAACGAGGUCGCCGCCCACGGCAUCUCUAAGGAGGACGCCGUCCAGGGCAUCGCGAACGAGGACGCCGCCCAGGGCAUCGCGAACGAGGACGCCGCCCAGGGCAUCGCACACGAGGACGCCGUCCAGGGCAUUGCUAACGAGGACGCCGUCCACGGCGUCGCUAAAGAGGUCGCCGCCCACGGCGUCGCUAACGAGGACCCUGUCCAGGGCGUCGCUAACGAGGACGUCGUCCAGGGCGUCGCUAACGAGGUUGAAGUCCAGGGCAUCGCACACGAGGACGCCGUCCAGGGCAUCGCUAACGAGGACGCCGCCCACGGCAUCGCUAACGAGGUCGCCGCCCACGGCGUCGCGAACGAGGACGCCGCCCAGGGCGUCGCUAACGAGGACGCCGCCCAGGGCGUCGCUAACGAGGACGCCGUCCACGGCGUCGCUAACGAGGACGCCGCCCAGGGCGUCGCUAAAGAGGUCACCGCCCACGGCGUCACUAACGAGGACGCCGUCCAGGGCGUCGUUAACCAGGAGGCCCUCCAUGGCGUCGUCGCUAACGAGGAUGCCGCCCAAGCGAUCGCUAAGCCGGACAGCGCCCAUGGCAUCGCUAACGAGGUCGCCGCCCAGGGCAUCGCUAACGAGGUCGCCGUCCACAGCAUCGCUAUCGAGGACACCACACCGUCCAGGGCGUGGCUAACGAGGUCGCUGCCCAGGGCAUCGCUACCGAGGAUGUCGCCGACGGCAUCGCUGAGGACGCCGCCCAUGGCAUCACUAACGAGGAGGCCGCCCAGGCCAUCGCUAAGCAGGAUGCCGCCCACAGCAUCACUAACGAGGAUGCCGUCCAGGGCGUCGCUAACGAGGACGCCGCCCACGGCGUCGCUAACGAGGACGCCGCCCAGGGCAUCGCUAACGAGGUCGCCACCCAUGGCAUCUCUAAGGAGGACGCCGUCCAGGGCAUCGCGAACGAGGACGCCGCCCAGGGCAUCGCGAACGAGGACGCCGCCCAGGGCAUCGCACACGAGGACGCCGUCCAGGGCAUUGCUAACGAGGACGCCGUCCACGGCGUCGCUAAAGAGGUCGCCGCCCACGGCGUCGCUAACGAGGAUGCCGCCCACGCGAUCGCUAAGCCGGACGCCGCCCGCGGCAUCGCUAACGAGGUCGCCACCCAGGGCAUCGCUACCCAGGAUGUCGCCGACGGCAUCGCUAACGAGGACGCCGCCCACGGCGUCGCUAACGAGGUCGCCGCCCACGGCAUCGCUAACGAGGUCGCCGUCCACUGCGUCGCUAUCGAGGACGCCGCCCAGGGCGUCGCUAAAGAGGUCACCGCCCACGGCGUCGCUAACGAGGACGCCGUCCAGGGCGUCGUUAACGAGUACGCCCUCCACAGCGUCGUCGCUAACGAGGAUGCCGCCCAAGCAAUCGCUAAGCCGGACGCCGCCCAUGGCAUCGCUAACGAGGUCGCCGCCCACAGCAUCGCGAACGAGGACGCUGCCCAGGGCAUCGCGAACGAGGACGCCGCCCAGGGCAUCGCUAACGAGGUCGCCGCCCACGGCAUCUCUAAGGAGGACGCCGUCCAGGGCAUCGCGAACGAGGACGCCGCCCAGGGCAUCGCGAACGAGGACGCCGCCCAGGGCAUCGCACACGAGGACGCCGUCCAGGGCAUUGCUAACGAGGACGCCGUCCACGGCGUCGCUAAAGAGGUCGCCGCCCACGGCGUCGCUAACGAGGACCCCGUCCAGGGCGUCGCUAACGAGGACGCCGUCCAGGGCGUCGCUAACGAGGUUGAAGUCCAGGGCGUCGCACACGAGGACGCCGUCCAGGGCAUCGCUAACGAGGACGCCGCCCACGGCAUCACUAACGAGGUCGCCGCCCACGGCAUCGCGAACGAGGACGCCGCCCAGGGCAUCGCGAACGAGGACGCCGCCCAGGGCAUCGCACACGAGGACGCCGUCCAGGGCAUCGCUAACGAGGACGCCGUCCACAGCGUCGCUAAAGAGGUCGCCGCCCAUGGCGUCGCUAACGAGGAUGCCGCCCACGCGAUCGCUAAGCCGGACGCCGCCCGCGGCAUCGCUAACGAGGUUGCCGCCCAGGGCAUCGCUACCGAGGAUGUCGCCGACGGCAUCGCUAACGAGGACGCCGCCCACGGCGUCGCUAACGAGGUCGCCGCCCACGGCAUCUCUAAGGAGGACGCCGUCCAGGGCAUCGCGAACGAGGACGCCGCCCAGGGCAUCGCUAAGGAGGACCCCAUCCAGGGCGUCGCUAACGAGGUUGAAGUCCAGGGCGUCGCACACGAGGACGCCGUCCAGGGCAUCGCUAACGAGGACGCCGCCCACGGCAUCGCCAACGAGGACGCUGCCCAGGGCAUCGCGAACGAGGACGCCGCCCAGGACAUCGCAAACGAGGACGCCGCCCAGGGCAUCGCUAAGGAGGACCCCGUCCAGGGCGUCGCUAACGAGGACCCCGUCCAGGGCGUCGCUAACGAGGACGCCGUCCAGGGCGUCGCUAACGAGGUUGAAGUCCAGGGCGUCGCACACGAGGACGCCGUCCAGGGCAUCGCUAACGAGGACGCCGCCCACGGCAUCGCUAACGAGGUCGCCGCCCACGGCAUCGCGAACGAGGACGCCGCCCAGGGCAUCGCGAACGAGGACGCCGCCCAGGGCAUUGCACACGAGGACGCCGUCCAGGGCAUCGCUAACGAGGACGCCGUCCACGGCGUCGCUAAAGAGGUCGCCGCCCACGGCGUCGCUAACGAGGAUGCCGCCCACGCGAUCGCUAAGCCGGACGCCGCCCGCGGCAUCGCUAACGAGGUCGCCGCCCAGGGCAUCGCUACCGAGGAUGUCGCCGACGGCAUCGCUAACGAGGACGCCGCCCACGGCGUCGCUAACGAGGAUGCCGCCCAAGCGAUCGCUAAGCCGGACGCCGCCCAUGGCAUCGCUAAUGAGGUCGCCGCCCAGGGCAUCGCUAACGAGGUCGCCGUCCACAGCAUCGCUAUCGAGGACACCACACCGUCCAGGGCGUGGCUAACGAAGUCGCUGCCCAGGGCAUUGCUACCGAGGAUGUCGCCGACGGCAUCGCUGAGGACGCCGUCCAGGGCAUCACUAACGAGGAGGCCGCCCAGGCCAUCGCU